ACCCUGCGCGCUUCUCCCAGAGGAGGGAGAGGGAAGAGGCGAGGGCGCAGCCCCAAGCCGAGUCCAGCAAGUCUGUCAAUCGGACGUGAACGUCCCGACGAGACAACUUGAACCUCAGGGCCCUCGCGCCAGCCGGACACCGCAGCCCCAUAAUAUUCCGGACCCCUGCUCCCCGUGCAGGUGGUGCAAACGCCCCUGCUCUCCGGCGCCCCCUGCCGGGAAGAGGGAAGGCGGCGGCGGCCGCGGAGGAGCAGGACGCUUGGUCCGGACGGAGCUCGGCGCUGGGAAGAAGCCGGGAGCUUCCCUGAUGGUGCCGCCGCCUCCGAGCCGGGGAGGAGCUGCCAGGGGCCAGCUGGGCAGGAGCCUGGGUCCGCUGCUGCUGCUCCUGGCGUUGGGACACACGUGGACCUACAGAGAGGAGCCGGAGGACGGCGACAGAGAAAUCUGCUCAGAGAGCAAAAUCGCGACGACUAAAUACCCGUGUCUGAAGUCUUCAGGCGAGCUCACCACAUGCUACAGGAAAAAGUGCUGCAAAGGAUAUAAAUUUGUUCUUGGACAAUGCAUCCCAGAAGAUUACGACGUUUGUGCCGAGGCUCCCUGUGAACAGCAGUGCACGGACAACUUUGGCCGAGUGCUGUGUACUUGUUAUCCGGGAUACCGAUAUGACCGGGAGAGACACCGGAAGCGGGAGAAGCCAUACUGUCUGGAUAUUGAUGAGUGUGCCAGCAGCAAUGGGACGCUGUGUGCCCACAUCUGCAUCAAUACCUUGGGCAGCUACCGCUGCGAGUGCCGGGAAGGCUACAUCCGGGAAGAUGAUGGGAAGACAUGUACCAGGGGAGACAAAUAUCCCAAUGACACUGGCCAUGAGAAGUCUGAGAACAUGGUGAAAGCCGGAACUUGCUGUGCCACAUGCAAGGAGUUCUACCAGAUGAAGCAGACCGUGCUGCAGCUGAAGCAAAAGAUUGCUCUGCUCCCCAACAAUGCAGCUGACCUGGGCAAGUAUAUCACUGGUGACAAGGUGCUGGCCUCAAACACCUACCUUCCAGGACCUCCUGGCCUGCCUGGGGGCCAGGGCCCUCCCGGUGAGUGUGGAAGAGGGCACAGGAGGGUGAUCACCAACAGAAAAAGCCUGCCAAAAGCUCACAUUUGCUGGGGCCUGGACAAUGUUCUCCAGCUUCCAUCGAGGAGAAACAAGGCUCACCAGGACCAAAGGGAAGCCCAGGCUUCCCCGGUAUGCCAGGCCCUCCUGGGCAGCCCGGCCCACGGGGCUCAAUGGGACCCAUGGGACCAUCUCCUGAUCUGUCCCACAUUAAGCAAGGCCGGAGGGGCCCUGUGGGUCCACCAGGGGCACCAGGAAGAGAUGGUUCUAAGGGGGAGAGAGGAGCGCCUGGGCCCAGAGGGUCUCCAGGACCCCCUGGUUCUUUCGACUUCCUGCUACUUAUGCUGGCUGACAUCCGCAAUGACAUCACUGAGCUGCAGGAAAAGGUGUUCGGGCACCGGACUCACUCUUCAGCAGAGGAGUUCCCUUUACCUCAGGAAUUUCCCAGCUACCCAGAAGCCAUGGACCUGGGCUCUGGAGAUGACCAUCCAAGAAGAACUGAGACAAGAGACUUGAGAGCCCCCAGAGACUUCUACCCAUAGCACAUCCCAACACCGUCACGCCAAAGGAAGAGAAAGAUCAACUCACCUGCAGUUAAACCAUCUAAAGAGAAGAAAGACCACUGGAGACCUAGAAAACAUACAUUUUUCUCUUCUCUUCUCCUGACGUCUCUCCACUCCUCUUCUUCCAAAUACGAUGCUAUUUUCAGAGUCCCCUCCUAGGCCUGCAGACAUGAGGGAGUGAAUGAUUGAUUUACCUGCUUCUCACUAAGAGUCCAUUGGGGUGGUUUGCAUUGUAACUUUUCUUUUACAUCCUAUUUUUCCAGGAACUUUGGAUUUAAGUACUCUCACAGUGUCUUAAAUCAUAAAUUCUUGAAGUUAAAUUUGGCAGAGUAUCAAAAGGGGGAAAAUGACAAAGUGAGCUCUAAGAAAAUGUGAGGCUACUUCUAAGAUGUGUGUUCACAAUAGACCAUAACUCCUCUAGUAUCAAAAUUGGGGCUCUUCAGUUAAAAAGGGGUGGGGAGGACAAACGUGUCGAUGUGCUUUGGUGGAGAAUUUUUUCCUUGUGCUUCUAGUAGACUUUAAAUAUUGUAUCCCUUUGUCAAACCUUGUUUCCCAAAUUCAAUUAAAGAGAGGAGAGAAUUGAAUGGCGUUUAGAGAAGAUAGAAAAGAAUCACAGUCAUAUAUUUACUGUUAUAUAGAUUGCCACAUUCUAAAAUUCAAAUACGGUGCUUAAGGUUUCAUGCCAUGCUUAUCUGUAAGUAUCCUAUUUAGGGAAGAAGAUUAAACUCUCUUUUCAAAAAAACAAAGUGAAAUGCCUGGAUUCACAUUAAAACAAUGGGCUCUCGUUUGCUAUAAUAUUUUAAAGCUGUUUAAUCAACAGUGGAGUCUGCUCUAUAAAUAUAGAUUAUUUGUUCAAUAAACUGGCUGAGCUUAGAGAGAGGUGCAGAAUUCCUGGUUCUGAGCAGGUGCCCAGAAGGUACCAUUAGGUGCCAUGAUCCAGGCUGAACCAAUAUACAGUGGGGCUGAAGUCUGCAAGGAGGUUGCUGGCUUGGGCUGACCUCACUAAUGCCAUCAGCAGCGGUAGGUAAAUUUUUUCUCCUUGGGUAUUACAAGUUUUUGUCUGGAGCCAACCAAGCUUGCCACCAACAUAUUGAGAGUAAUACACUAUUGAAAGUUAUCUUGGAUGGGGAGAAAAAAAAAUAGUGGUUUUCCUUGUUUGCAAAAACUUCCUUCCUAUUCUCAUUUUUUCUUAAUUUUCUUUAAUUUAGUCCAAGUUCCAGUUCUUUUAGGCCUUCUCUUUGAUUUAUUUUCCCCUGCAUGUGAGAAGCAGUUCAGAAAAAGGUCUAUAUCUCCACCUCCUAGUGAGUUAGAGUGUUUUCUCAGAGCACCUCUGGGUGGCAAAGGGAAGCAUGUUCCUGCCAAGGUUUGCUGUGGAUUCAGAAGCACCAGGAGCAAGAGACCAGAAGGAUGAUCUGCUCCUUUGUAACGUUGUUGAGGGCCCUCUUGUUUCCAAUGAGCAGCUUAUAGGUUACUCACAGUCCACUUUCUCACUGGACACACAAAGUGGCUCUUUAUCUACCUUUGCGGGAGAUUUUCACUCUCCUGCAAAUGAUCGUUCUCACACUCAUAUUAGCUCAUGUUGGAAUUUCCCAUCCUGCCAUGUCCUUUCCCAUUUCUUUUUGGCUUUUUUGCCUCCACCUUUUAGCCCACAUCAUUUAACUCCACUACUGUGAAAGCUUGCUUAAAGAAAAUCCCUCUUGGCCGGGUGUGGUAGCCCACGCCUCUAAUCCCAGCACUUUGGGAGGCUGAGGCGGGGAGAUCACAAGGUCAGGAGAUCGAGACCAGCCUGACCAACAUGGUGAAACCCUGUCUCUACUAAAAAUACAAAAAUUAGCUGGGCGUGUUGGCACACACCUGUAAUCCCAGCUACUCAGGAGGCUGAGGCAGGAGAAUUACUUUAACCUGCGGGGGGAGCCUAGAUUGCGCUACUGCACUCCAGCCUAGGCAACAGAGGGAGACUCUGUCUCAUUAAAAAAAAAAAAAAAAAAAAAAAAAGGCCGGGCUUGGUGGCUCAUGCCUGUAAUCCCAGCACUUUGGGAGGCCGAGGCGGGCGGAUCACGAGGUCAGGAGAUCGAGACCACAGUGAAACCCUGUCUCUACUAAAAACACAAAAAAUUAGUCGGGCGUGGUGGUGGGCGCCUGUGGUCCCAGCUGCUCGGGAGGCUGAGGCAGGAGAAUGGCGUGAACCUGGGAGGCGGAGCUUGCGCUGAGCCGAGAUCGUGCCACUGCACUCCAGCCUGGGCGACAGAGCGAGACUCUGUCUCAAAAAAAAAAAAAUAUCCCUUUUGUUGUGUUUGAAUGCCACCUUUCAGUCUUCUUCCUUAAGAAUGUUAGGAAGGGGCUUUGCAAACCUCUAGUGGCAACAGUCUUCCUUCCCUUCUUCCUACCACGUUGGAAAUGCAGGACUCAUGUCAGUCAGCAUGUGACCGAGUCUUUCAUGAACACUUUGCUCCUCUAUGUCUCAUUUAUGCAAAAUUCCUGGUGACUCUCCACUAACAUUUUUAAAGUGAAAGCAAACUUUCACUUUAAAAAAAGUGAGCGAGAGGAUCCCUUGAGCCCAGGAGUUCAAGGCCAGUCUGGGCAACAUAGCAAGACCCCAUCCCUAAAAAAAAAAAAAUAAGUUUUAUUAAAUGUGGCACUUUCCCCUAGAAGGGCAGUAACCCCAGGAACCAGUCUGCCUCUUUUCGAAUAAAGGAGACUUUUUAAAAAGAAAAAAUUUCUUUUUAGGGUGGGGUGCUCUUUAUCUAGCAUCUUUCCUUCCUCCUUCUCUCUGCAAAAUUCAACAUUCAUGACAGAGGGCCACACCAACCACGGGUUUAUAGAGAGAGGAACUGAACAGCUGUUGAUUCCCAUCUGGAAUAUAUUUAAUGUUUGCCUGCUUGUGGAGCAUGGUAUUUAAAGGGUGUGGAUGGAUGAAUGUUUAAAAAAAAACACACAAAACUAUGCACAAGCUGUAUGAGAGAUGGCUAGGUCCAUCUAUGAUUUUUUUUAAAAGAAGAAUUUUAAUACCUUUUCUUUGACAGUGAACUGUAUUUAGAAAUAUGAUCUUUAUUGUGAAAUGCUCAUAAAAUGCAACCAAACUGCAUGUUUGGCCAUAGGCUAGAAUAAUAUAUUAAAAGAAUUAAUGGAAAGUAGUAUUGUCUGGGUUUCAUGAAACUAUUCCAGAUAAUAUUCUCCAGCAAAACUUAUGGUAACCUGUAUUUUAUAAUGUCAAUCUGCUGGACCAAGUUAAUUUAGAAAAUAAUUUUUAAUCCUCAGAUUUUCAAAACUUGGACUACUGCAAGACUGAUAUGUACUUUUUAUGCCCAAAUCAUAUUUUUCAAAGAUAGGACAUCAUAAGGCAUCAUUAUUUCUAAUGUAUCUUUUAACUAGAUAGAAAAAGCUUUACUGUCUAAACAGGACUUCUGCUCAAAACCUAAUGGGAAAGCUAUUUCUGGGGUAAGAUUUGUAACAGUGCUUCUAGGUCAUUUCAUGUUUUAUAGGGAAAAAGAUCUUUGUACACCUCCUCAACCUGUUAGUAGAAAUGUUGACUUCGAUUUUUUGCACCCUCUUCACAGGACCUCAUAAGUUGCCUCUGUUCUUGGAAAGCAAUGGGAAUAAAAAUAUGCUGUUGAAAAUAGUGCAUGGGGCCAGGCACAGUGGUUAUGCCUGUAAUCCCAACACUUUGGGAGGCUGAGGCGGGCGCAUCAUGAGGUCAGGAGAUCAAGACCAUCCUGACCAACACGUGGUGAAACCCCAUCUCUACUAAAAUAAAUAAAAAAAAAAAUUAGCCAGGCGUGGUGGUGCACGCCUGUAGUCUCAGCUACUCGGGAAGCUGAGACACAAGAAUUGCUUGAACCCGGGAGGUGGAGGUUGCAGUGAGCCAAGAUUGCGCCACUGCACUCCAGCCUGGCUACAGAGUGAGACUCCGUCUCGAAAAAAGAAAAUAGUACAUGGAGGGCAUGCAUUUUAGUUUAGGAAACCCCCCUCCCUUCCCAGUUCCAGAGGGAGAAAUUAUAAGCUAUACUGUGCCAAAAGUGAGUGGGGCUGCAGAGAGAAUGGUGCCUUUUCUCACCUUCUGAGUUAAUGCCCGACAUCUGCCAUUGGAUUCAUUGACCAAAGGAAGUCAUUUCUACUGUAUAAACUCAGGAGUAUCAUAGCCCAACAAGUAAAUAAUAAAUGUUCAUUGGUUUUGGAAGGAAGGAAAGGUGAGUAUUACCCCACCAAAUACCAGCGAAGAGCACCCUGGCUUUGGCCAUCUUUCCAAGGUUCAUAAUUGCUGUGGGCCUGGUGAGCCCUGUUCCCAGGUAUGCAAGGGAGGGCUUCUCCAGGCCAGACAUUUCUGUAGGUUUUCAGGUAGCAACUCCCCCAUCAUAUUUUGGGUGUCAUUCCCCACUCUCUCUCCCCACUUCUCAGCCUGUGCCCCAGAAACAACCACAGCAGCCUCAUUCUGCAGACUUAACAUCUGUCAAAUAACCUUCCUGAAAAGGAAAGUUAUUGGAGGAAUCCAGGCCAAACAACAAGUAGAAUAGAGCCAUCUAAAGUUAUUAAUAAUGAGUUCAGGGAAAUAGAUGAAUUUUUUCCUGGCAUAGUCAAUAUUUAUAUCUCACAACAAGUCAAAAAUAAUUUUCCAUUUGGAAAACAAAACACACCAUGACUGUAAUUGUUAAGGCAUAUAAUCAUGAACUUCACAUGCUCCCUCAACAAACGUUACUGCUCUAGGGAAAUCAUAGAAAAGGACCCUCUUACUCCCCAGGGGAUCAAAGCAAGUCCCCUUAGGAAUUUCAUGUGUGCCGUGGGUCUGUUUUUAUUUCACAGUGACUAGUCAUAUACUGGAGUAGCUCUGUUGUUCAUUAUUUGUAACAGGUCCAUGUAACAGUCAAGUUAGCAUUCAAGCAAUUAUGGAUGUGAUACUAUGAUGUACUUUUGUUAUGAUUGUAUAUGCUUAAUAACAAAGUUAUUUUUCUUA